GUUAUUAUUCCUCACAAUAACCAGAUAGCCUCUGCUUUCUUUUUCCUUUCUUCGGAAUGAGAGACUCAACCAUAAUAGAAAGAAUGGAGAACUAUUAACCACCAUUCUUCAGUGGGCUGUGAUUUUCAGAGGGGAAUACUAAGAAAUGGUUUUCCAUACUGGAACCCAAAGGUAAAGACACUCAAGGACAGACAUUUUUGGCAGAGCAUAGAUGAAAAUGGCAAGUUCCCUGGCUUUCCUUCUGCUCAACUUUCAUGUCUCCCUCUUCUUGGUCCAGCUGCUCACUCCUUGCUCAGCUCAGUUUUCUGUGCUUGGACCCUCUGGGCCCAUCCUGGCCAUGGUGGGUGAAGACGCUGAUCUGCCCUGUCACCUGUUCCCGACCAUGAGUGCAGAGACCAUGGAGCUGAGGUGGGUGAGUUCCAGCCUAAGGCAGGUGGUGAACGUGUAUGCAGAUGGAAAGGAAGUGGAAGACAGGCAGAGUGCACCGUAUCGAGGGAGAACUUCGAUUCUGCGGGAUGGCAUCACUGCAGGGAAGGCUGCUCUCCGAAUACACAACGUCACAGCCUCUGACAGUGGAAAGUACUUGUGUUAUUUCCAAGAUGGUGACUUCUACGAAAAAGCCCUGGUGGAGCUGAAGGUUGCAGCAUUGGGUUCUGAUCUUCACAUUGAAGUGAAGGGUUAUGAGGAUGGAGGGAUCCAUCUGGAGUGCAGGUCCACUGGCUGGUACCCCCAACCCCAAAUAAAGUGGAGCGACACCAAGGGAGAGAACAUCCCGGCUGUGGAAGCACCUGUGGUUGCAGAUGGAGUGGGCCUGUAUGCAGUAGCAGCAUCUGUGAUCAUGAGAGGCAGCUCUGGUGGGGGUGUAUCCUGCAUCAUCAGAAAUUCCCUCCUCGGCCUGGAAAAGACAGCCAGCAUAUCCAUCGCAGACCCCUUCUUCAGGAGCGCCCAGCCCUGGAUCGCGGCCCUGGCAGGGACCCUGCCUAUCUCGUUGCUGCUUCUCGCAGGAGCCAGUUACUUCUUGUGGAGACAACAGAAGGAAAAAAUUGCUCUGUCCAGGGAGACAGAAAGAGAGCGAGAGAUGAAAGAAAUGGGAUACGCUGCAACAGAGCAAGAAAUAAGCCUAAGAGAGAAGCUCCAGGAGGAACUCAAGUGGAGGAAAAUCCAGUACAUGGCUCGUGGAGAGAAGUCUUUGGCCUAUCAUGAAUGGAAAAUGGCCCUCUUCAAACCUGCGGAUGUGAUUCUGGAUCCAGACACGGCAAACGCCAUCCUCCUUGUUUCUGAGGACCAGAGGAGUGUGCAGCGUGCUGAAGAGCCGCGGGAUCUGCCAGACAACCCUGAGAGAUUUGAAUGGCGUUACUGUGUCCUUGGCUGUGAAAACUUCACAUCAGGGAGACAUUACUGGGAGGUGGAAGUGGGGGACAGAAAAGAGUGGCAUAUUGGGGUAUGUAGUAAGAACGUGGAGAGGAAAAAAGGUUGGGUCAAAAUGACACCGGAGAACGGAUACUGGACUAUGGGCCUGACUGAUGGGAAUAAGUAUCGGGCUCUCACUGAGCCCAGAACCAACCUGAAACUUCCUGAGCCUCCUAGGAAAGUGGGGAUCUUCCUGGACUAUGAGACUGGAGAGAUCUCGUUCUAUAAUGCCACAGAUGGAUCUCAUAUCUACACCUUUCCGCACGCCUCUUUCUCUGAGCCUCUAUAUCCUGUUUUCAGAAUUUUGACCUUGGAGCCCACUGCCCUGACCAUUUGCCCAAUACCAAAAGAAGUAGAGAGUUCCCCCGAUCCUGACCUAGUGCCUGAUCAUUCCCUGGAGACACCACUGACCCCGGGCUUAGCUAAUGAAAGUGGGGAGCCUCAGGCUGAAGUAACAUCUCUGCUUCUCCCUGCCCACCCUGGAGCUGAGGUCUCCCCUUCUGCAACAACCAAUCAGAACCAUAAGCUACAGGCACGCACUGAAGCACUUUACUGAUAUUCAUUCCAUUAUUCCAUAUGACAGUUGUUUUGAGUUUCGUACCACCUUAUUGUCCCCUUAUACAGAUAAGGAAACUGGGGUGCAGAAAGGUGAAUUAACUUUACAAAGUAGACAUGACAAGUGAACAGCAGAGCUGGGAUCUAAACAGCAAUAACUAACAUUAACAGAGAAUUUAAAAUGUUCUUAGUGCUGUGUUAUAAGCUUUGGUGGAUGUCACUCCUUUAAUCCUCACAACACCCUGUCGGGUAGUCAUAUUUUGCAAGUAUGGAAGCUGAGGCAGGGCAACAUGAAGUAACUUACAUAACUCAUACAGUAAUUUGUGCAGUUGGGAGAUGUUCAGCCUUAGUCCCUGGCUAAUUGCCUGUUCUUUUCCAGCCUGAUUUUUUUUCCCACAGGAAGAGCCCACAUGUAGCCCUGAGGUUUCCUUCCCAGGACAGCUGCAGGGUAGAGAUCAUUUUAAGUGCUUGUGGAGUUGACAUCCCUAUUGACUCUUUCCCAGCUGAUAUCAGAGACUUAGACCCAGCACUCCUUGGAUUAGCUCUGCAGAGUGUCUUGGUUGAGAGAAUAACCUCAUAGUACCAACAUGACAUGUGACUUGGAAAGAGACUAGAGGCCACACUUGAUAAAUCAUGGGGCACAGAUAUGUUCCCACCCAACAAAUGUGAUAAGUGAUUGUGCAGCCAGAGCCAGCCUUCCUUCAAUCAAGGUUUCCAGGCAGAGCAAAUACCCUAGAGAUUCUCUGUGAUAUAGGAAAUUUGGAUCAAGGAAGCUAAAAGAAUUACAGGGAUGUUUUUAAUCCCACUAUGGACUCAGUCUCCUGGAAAUAGGUCUGUCCACUCCUGGUCAUUGGUGGAUGUUAAACCCAUAUUCCUUUCAACUGCUGCCUGCUAGGGAAAACUGCUCCUCAUUAUCAUCACUAUUAUUGCUCACCACUGUAUCCCCUCUACUUGGCAAGUGGUUGUCAAGUUCUAGUUGUUCAAUAAAUGUGUUAAUAAUGCUUA